AAAGAGUCCUGGAAAGACAACCUUCAGGUCCAGCCCUGGAGCUGGAGGAGUGGAGCCCCACUCUGAAGACGCAGCCUUUCUCCAGGUUCUGUCUCUCCCAUUCUGAUUCUUGACACCAGAUGCAGGAUGGUGUCCUCUCCCUGCACGCAGGCAAGCUCACGGACUUGCUCCCGUAUCCUGGGACUGAGCCUUGGGACUGCAGCCCUGUUUGCUGCUGGGGCCAACGUGGCACUCCUCCUUCCUAACUGGGAUGUCACCUACCUGUUGAGGGGCCUCCUUGGCAGGCAUGCCAUGCUGGGAACUGGGCUCUGGGGAGGAGGCCUCAUGGUACUCACUGCAGCUAUCCUCAUCUCCUUGAUGGGCUGGAGAUACGGCUGCUUCAGUAAGAGUGGGCUCUGUCGAAGCGUGCUUACUGCUCUGUUGUCAGGUGGCCUGGCUUUACUUGGAGCCCUGAUUUGCUUUGUCACUUCUGGAGUUGCUCUGAAAGAUGGUCCUUUUUGCAUGUUUGAUGUUUCAUCCUUCAAUCAGACACAAGCUUGGAAAUAUGGUUACCCAUUCAAAGACCUGCAUAGUAGGAAUUAUCUGUAUGACCGUUCGCUCUGGAACUCCGUCUGCCUGGAGCCCUCUGCAGCUGUUGUCUGGCACGUGUCCCUCUUCUCCGCCCUUCUGUGCAUCAGCCUGCUCCAGCUUCUCCUGGUGGUCGUUCAUGUCAUCAACAGCCUCCUGGGCCUUUUCUGCAGCCUCUGCGAGAAGUGACAGGCAGAACCUUCACUUGCAAGCAUGGGUGUUUUCAUCAUCGGCUGUCUUGAAUCCUUUCUACAAGGAGUGGGUACGAAUUAUAAACAAACUUCCCCUUUAGGUAUCCCUGGAGUAAUAAUGACAACAAAAUUCACUGCAGGUCGGUGGAAUGAUAGAAUGCAUUUUAAAUCACAUUGUAAACUUCCAGGUGAUCCAUGGAUAGGAUAAAUAACUAAGUUAUUAUAAUUGUUUAGGAAUUUAUAGUCCAUAAAAUAUCCUCCAGCCAGG